GUAGUUCCCUGGAGCCCGGCCCUGCGUUCCGCUGACUUAGAGGGAUCUCCAAGCGUCCCUCGUCUCCCCCAAACUCCUUAAUCCCGCCCGUCCGACCUAGAGUCUAGUCCUCCGACGGGGUGAUGGGAUAGGAUGGGACAGAAGAGGAAGGGGCUUAAGUCACUGCAGCCAGAGGGAUGGAGGUGGACUGAAGGGAGGGCUUCUCCGGUGGGGUUAGAAGGGAAAAGUAGGGAAAGAGAAGUGUAAGGUAGAUGGCAGAGGCAGAGACAUGGAAAGACAGACUCUAGGGUUCCUGAUGAAAUCUAUCUCGGCCAACACAAAAGGGAGGGUACAGUGGUGGGGGGCACCCAAGCUAGGGUGUGAGUACCCUAAGUGUAUUCUUCUGAGAUGUAGGCCAUUCACUAACUCUUGGAACAGCUACAGUUUCACAGUAGGAAGACCCCCCCAGAUUCACUGCCCCUCCCUUAGUAAAGCCUCUGAGACCUUCCUGAACAUUCCCUUCUGUCUUUGCCCUCUGUUCCUUCCAGAGACCAUGUGCCCAGGCAGAUGGAUUCCUCCCGGGCCUGAGAGGAACUGCAGGAAUUCUCCUGCCUCUUACCCGUAAAACCCCAACUUCUCUAGCCCUAGGGCAGGAAGUCCCAAACAAUUUCUACCCCUUUUUCUGCAAUUCUCAUUGGGGUGAGAGGAGGCCCAGGAGGAGAGAGAGCUGGGCUCAGCUUCUUUUUGAGCUGCUGGAGCCCUCUGUGAGGAGGCCCUCUUUGCUGGCUUCUCAGGAGAGCGUGGCUAGGUUCUGCCUGCCUAUGGGAAGAGGGGGCCAGGGUGUGUGGAGCAAGAUGGUGGCGGUGCUGGUGCCUUGGGACCUGGGGGAAUGGGACAGCUGGUCGGCUCAGAGACGGCCUACUUUACUCACAGCUGGAAUUUAGUGGGGAGAAGCAGCUCAACUCCAAUCCUGGAGGAUUAGGGAGAUUAAAGUGAGAGAAGAGAGAGAUGUCCCAGAGACCAAGAGCUCCCAGGUCAGCCCUCUGGCUCCUGGCACCCCCACUGCUGCGGUGGGCACCCCCACUCCUCACAGUGCUGCAUAGCGACCUCUUCCAGGCCUUGCUGGACAUCCUGGACUAUUAUGAGGCUUCCCUCUCAGAGAGUCAGAAAUACCGCUACCAAGAUGAAGACACGCCCCCUCUGGAGCACAGCCCGGCCCACCUCCCCAACCAGGCCAAUUCUCCCCCAGUGAUUGUCAACACAGAUACCCUAGAAGCCCCAGGAUAUGAGUUGCAGGUGAACGGGACCGAGGGGGAGAUGGAAUACGAGGAAAUCACAUUGGAAAGGGGUAACUCAGGUCUGGGCUUCAGCAUCGCAGGUGGCACUGACAACCCACACAUCGGUGACGACCCAUCCAUUUUCAUCACCAAGAUCAUUCCUGGUGGGGCUGCGGCCCAGGAUGGCCGCCUCAGGGUCAACGACAGCAUCCUGUUUGUAAAUGAAGUGGACGUGCGCGAGGUGACCCACUCAGCGGCGGUGGAAGCCCUCAAAGAGGCAGGCUCCAUCGUUCGCCUCUAUGUCAUGCGCCGGAAGCCCCCGGCUGAGAAGGUCAUGGAGAUCAAGCUCAUCAAGGGGCCUAAAGGUCUUGGCUUCAGCAUCGCAGGGGGCGUAGGGAACCAGCACAUCCCAGGAGAUAAUAGCAUCUAUGUAACAAAGAUCAUCGAAGGGGGUGCUGCCCACAAGGAUGGGAGGUUGCAGAUUGGAGACAAGAUCCUGGCGGUCAACAGUGUGGGGCUAGAGGACGUCAUGCAUGAAGAUGCUGUGGCAGCCCUGAAGAACACGUAUGAUGUUGUCUACCUAAAGGUGGCCAAGCCCAGCAAUGCCUACCUGAGUGACAGCUAUGCUCCCCCAGACAUCACAACCUCUUAUUCCCAGCACCUGGACAAUGAGAUCAGUCACAGCAGCUACCUGGGCACCGACUACCCCACAGCCAUGACCCCCACUUCCCCUCGGCGCUACUCUCCAGUGGCCAAGGACCUGCUCGGGGAGGAAGACAUUCCCCGAGAACCGAGGCGAAUUGUGAUCCACCGGGGCUCCACGGGCCUGGGCUUCAACAUCGUGGGUGGCGAGGACGGUGAAGGCAUCUUCAUCUCCUUUAUCCUGGCCGGGGGCCCUGCAGACCUCAGUGGGGAGCUGCGGAAGGGGGACCAGAUCCUGUCGGUCAACGGUGUGGACCUCCGAAAUGCCAGCCAUGAGCAGGCUGCCAUUGCCCUGAAGAAUGCGGGUCAGACGGUCACGAUCAUCGCUCAGUAUAAACCAGAAGAGUACAGCCGAUUCGAGGCCAAGAUCCACGACCUUCGGGAACAGCUCAUGAACAGCAGCCUGGGCUCAGGGACUGCGUCCCUGCGGAGCAACCCCAAAAGGGGUUUCUACAUCAGGGCCCUGUUUGAUUACGACAAGACCAAGGACUGCGGCUUCCUGAGCCAGGCCCUGAGCUUCCGCUUUGGGGAUGUGCUGCAUGUCAUCGAUGCUAGUGAUGAGGAGUGGUGGCAGGCACGGCGGGUCCACUCUGACAGUGAGACCGACGACAUUGGGUUCAUCCCCAGCAAACGGCGGGUUGAGCGACGAGAGUGGUCAAGGUUAAAGGCCAAGGACUGGGGCUCCAGCUCUGGAUCGCAGGGUCGAGAAGACUCGGUUCUGAGCUACGAGACAGUGACGCAGAUGGAAGUGCACUAUGCUCGCCCCAUCAUCAUCCUUGGGCCCACCAAGGACCGCGCCAACGAUGAUCUUCUCUCCGAGUUCCCCGACAAGUUUGGAUCCUGUGUUCCCCAUACGACACGGCCCAAGCGGGAGUAUGAGAUAGAUGGCCGGGAUUACCACUUUGUGUCGUCCCGGGAGAAAAUGGAGAAGGACAUUCAGGCGCACAAGUUCAUUGAGGCCGGCCAGUACAACAGCCACCUCUAUGGGACCAGCGUCCAGUCCGUGCGAGAGGUGGCAGAGCAGGGGAAGCACUGCAUCCUCGAUGUCUCGGCCAAUGCCGUGCGGCGGCUGCAGGCGGCCCACCUGCACCCCAUCGCCAUCUUCAUCCGCCCCCGCUCCCUGGAGAAUGUGCUAGAGAUUAACAAGCGGAUCACAGAGGAGCAAGCCCGCAAAGCCUUCGACAGAGCCACCAAGCUGGAGCAGGAGUUCACAGAGUGCUUCUCAGCCAUCGUGGAGGGUGACAGCUUUGAGGAGAUCUACCACAAGGUGAAGCGUGUCAUCGAGGACCUCUCAGGCCCCUACAUCUGGGUUCCAGCCCGAGAGAGACUCUGAUUCCUGCCCUGGCUUGGCCUGGACUCGCCCUGCCUCCAUCACCUGGGCCCUUGGUCUGGACUGAAUUGCCCAAGCCCUUGGCUCCCCCCGGCCUCCCUCCCACCCCUUCUUAUUUAUUUCCUUUCUAACUGGAUCCAGCCUGUUGGAGGGGGGACACUCCUCUGCAUGUAUCCCCGCACCCCAGAACUGGGCUCCUGAACGCCAGGAACCUGGGGUCUGGGGGGGAGCUGGGCUCCUUGUUCCGAGCCCUUGCUCCUUAGGAUCCCCGCCCCCACCUGCCCCCAAUGCACACACAGACCCACCGGGGGCCACCUGCCCUCCCCCAUCCUCUCCCACACACAUUCCAGAAGUCAGGGCCCCCUCGAGGAGCACCCGCUGCAGGGAUGCAGGGCCACAGGCCUCCGCUCUCUCCUAAGGCAGGGUCUGGGGUCACCCCUGCCCUCAUCGUAAUUCCCCAUGUUCCUUGAUUUCUCAUUUAUUUUUUCCACUUUUUUUCUUCUCAAAGGUGGUUUUUUGGGGGGAGAAGCAGGGGACUCCGCAGCGGGCCCCUGCCUUCCACAUGCCCCCACCAUUUUUCUUUGCCGGUUUGCAUGAGUGGAAGGUCUAAAUGUGGCUUUUUUUUUUUUUUUUCCUGGGAAUUUUUUUGGGGAAAAGGGAGGGAUGGGUCUAGGGAGUGGGAAAUGCGGGAGGGAGGGUGGGGGGCAGGGGUCGGGGGUCGGGUGUCCGGGAGCCAGGGAAGACUGGAAAUGCUGCCGCCUUCUGCAAUUUAUUUAUUUUUUUCUUUUGAGAGAGUGAAAGGAAGAGACAGAUACUUGAAACUUGGUGUGUGGCCUGGUUAUUUGGGACCUGGGUGUGGAGGGAGAUGGGCGCAGCAGAGUCAGAUCCUUCUUCACUCCAAGCCAGAGAGGUUAGUGGCCUGGAAAAUGGGCCAGGGAGGUAACUGGCAAAUCAAGGAACCCGAGUUGGUGAAGACUGAGCCUGGGAAGGUCUGGAGCUCUGUCCAAAGUCAUGACAGGCCAGAAAGGGGAGGCUGGAACUUGUCUGGGGCCCUGCAGACUUAGUCCAGCUCUGAUCCCUGCCGGGCUGUCUCAGUCCUGUUGGGAAGCACAACAGUCCUUAAAGGAAAAUAGAGAGGAAACUUCGUUCAUUCAUGUUCAUGGAGUUGUGGACAGAGCUAGGAUCUGGAAAUGAUUUUUUUUGUUUUUUUGUUUUUUUUUUUGAGACAGAGUCUUGCUCUGUCGCACAGGCUGGAGUGCAGUGGCUCGAUCUCGGCUCACUGUGAUCUCUGCCACCCUGGUUCAAGUGAUUCUCCUGCCUCAGCCCCCUGAGUAGCUGGGAUUACAGAUUACUGCCACCAUGCCUGGCUAAUUUUGUAUUUUUAGUAGAGAUGGGGUUUCACCAUGUUGGUCAGGCUGGUCUUGAACUCCUGACCUUGUUAUCCACCCGCCUCAGCCUCCCAAAGUGCUGGGAUUACAGGCGUGAGCCACCGCGCCUGGCCUGGAAAUGAUCUUUACAGAGUUCUGCUGAUAAGAACUGCUGUGUGAAUAUACGCUAGGUUUCUUUAUGCGCCCCCCCCACCCUUUUUUUUUUUUUUUUGAGACAGAGUUUCGCUCUUUCGCUCAGGCUGGAGUGCUGUGGUGCGAUCUUGGCUCACUGCAACCUCUGCCUGCUGGGUUCACACGGUUCUCCUGCCUCAGCCUCUCGAAUAGCUGGGAUUACAGGCGCCUGCCACCACUCCUGGCUAAUUUUUGUAUUUUUAGUAGAGAUGGGGUUUUGCUUUGUUGGCCAGGCUGGUCUCGAACUCCUGACCUCAGGUGAUCCGCCCAGCUUGGCCUCCCACAGUGUUAAGAUUACAGGCAUGAGCCACUACGCCCAGCCUUUAUGUCCUAUCUCUAUGGGAAAGAUCUGAGGCAGCUUUGUAAAUAAUGAGGGUAGGAAAAUAAGAAUCUAAAUGCCAAAGAUGAAAACUGGAGAAAUGUAUAUGAACUGUGAGGGUAAAUGUGAUCUCUGAGCUUCCUGAUAGCCAUGGCAAAAAAGGAAAUUGUCAAUUACCUACUUCUUUAUUAUAAGGGAGAAAUAAUUUUAGUUCUUUUAGGGAGUCAUAUUUUCCUGGCCCUAAGUCCUAACUGAAGCUCCUGAGAUCCUGCUAUGUAGAAUGGUGACUCUCAGCCUUCUGCCUUCUUCAUGUGUUUGGCACAGAUGAACCUUUGGGGGCACCUGCUGGGGUACUAUUCCUUUCUCUGAUUCUCAGGUGCUCCAGUGGGUAAGGCUGAGGCAGAGGGCCCUAAGAGUUAUGGUGGUUAAAUCCCAAACAGUGCAAAAGGGCAUUUUUUGUAGCCACUCCUGACUAAAGUUGAGAGUUUCAUGCAAAAGACCAACCCAGGGGUAGUGAUUCUGUGGAUGGCAUGGCCGUCCAAGCCUAAAGUAGUCCAAGAAUAGAGGCAGAGAUUGCUGAAGGGGUGUCACUUCAACCAGUAGCCACGUAUUGCCCUGCAGGAUUUUCUAUGCAGGACCGAGUCCAUCAGGAUCCUGGGGAUAGGGACCAGGGGUCUGCAUUUCUGGAAAGCUCCCGGGUGAUUUUGAUGUCUCACUGGGUGGAGAAGCACUGCUUCAGAGGAUUUUUUUUUUUUUUUUUUUGAGGUCGAGUUUCACUUUUGUUGCCCAAGCUGGAGUGCAAUGGCGCGAUCUCGGCUCACUGCAACCUCCAACUCCAGGGUUCAAGUGAUUCUCCUGCCUCAGCUUCCCAAGUAGCUGGGAUUACAGAUGCGUGCCAUAACACACAGCUAUUUUUUAAUAUUUUUAGUAGAAACGGGGUUUCACCAUGUUAGCCAAGCUGGUCUCAAACUCUUGACCUCAGGUGAUCUGCCCGCCUUGGCCUCCCAAAGUGCUGGGAUUACAGGCGUGAGCCACUGCACCUGGCCCUGAUGUUUUUCAAAUAAUCCUUCUCUUAGCUUGGUUCUGUGUAAUAGCAGAUGGCUUGAGGCUGUGAUAACGUUCUCUAUCGUGAGCUGAAGGGAGAAAUCUAGGAGCUGAGGAAGGUGUGUGCAGGUAAUGCGUCUGCGUGUUAAACUAGAAGGGGCAGAAUCACAUAUUUGACCUGGAUGGGGUAGAAUCACAUAAUUUUGCAUGUAUUAUUAUUAUUAUUAUUAUUAUUAUUAUUGGAGACAGAGUUUCGCUCUUGUUGCCCAGGCUGGAGUGCAGUGGUGCGAUCUCUGCUCACUGCAACCUCUGCCUUCCGGAUUCAAGCUAUUCUCCUGCCUCAGCCUCCCGAGUAGCUGGGAUUACAGGUGCAUGCCACCACGCCCAGCUAAUUUUUUGUAUUUAGUAGAGAUGGGGAUUUCACCAUAUUGAUCAGGCUGGUCUCGAACUCCUGACCUCGGGUGAUCCACCCCCCCCCCCCUCGGCCUCCCAAAGUGCUAGGAUUACAGGCAUGAGCCACCGCGCCUGGCCUGCAUGCAUUAUUUUGUAAAUUAUAAUCAGUACACGUACCUGACAACAAUUCAAAUAAAUAUAGAAAUACA